AUGACGAGGGGCCUCCUGCCACCCAAAAUAUCUCUCCGCAGCCCUCGGGUGCGGGGCGCGCGCGCCACGAGCCCCCCGCCCGCUCGCUGCCGCGCGGUCCCGCCCCCAGGGCCGACGGCAGGCGCGCGAGGCGCGUGCGCGUGCGCGUGCCGGCACGAGGCCGGAGCCCAGGGUCUGUCUGGCAGGCAGACAGGUGCCAGCAGCUCGCAGCCUGGCGUUCCCGCUCUGGGGGCCGUCCGGGAACAGAGGCGCGCGAAGUGCGCGUGCGCGGCGGCGGAGGCGGUGGCGGCGCGAGGCAGAGCCAGAGCCCGGGGUCGGUCAAUCAGGUGCGGGCGGCUGGAGCAUGGCUUUGUGAGGCCUCUGAGGGGACCCGGCGGUGGCGGCCACGGCGGGACGGGCCGCCCACCAGUUGAACUCCGACAGCUGAGGCGGCUGAGGAGAUUAGACUCCAGAGAUAAUGAUAUUAGGAAAUCCAAACUGAAAUGGACCCCAGAGCAAUUGAAGAAAGAAAGAGUCAAGGGAGGAUCCCAACGUGGCAGGGAGGCUUGCAAGGGGAGGCCGAGGCACUGGUGCAAGCAAACUAUAAUGACUAAGGUGAGAUUGUUUACUCAGGCAACAUAUGCAGAUGCAUCUUAUUUAUACUUCUUAUUGUAAAUAAUAGUCAUGUUAAUCAAAGAACACCAUAAAAUUUGAAUUGCUCUGUGUUAUGCGUAAGAUGGACAUCAUACUUACCACAUGCUUAUCCAUAGUGUGGGGAACCAUGGUAUGAUACCAGUUGGAAGACAAAGGUGCCAUGGUUGGAAACAAAACCCUAAAUUGCAAGGAGGAAACAAUUGCCUGAAAAGAGACUCCAGAUGAGCCCUAUAA